GCAUUUCUGCGCAGCUCUAGCGCGCCUCGGAGCCCGCCGGGGCAGCCGCCGGACACCAGGACCGCGAGCCAGACAGCUCCCGGAAGCCGCGCCGCCGCCGCCAGCCACAGCACAGCCGGACAGAGGAGGUGGAUUAGGAGUUCCCGGGAGGGAGCCUGCUCAGCCUUUCCCUGACAUUUGGGCAAAUGUGUGGGGAGAUGCGGAGCUCAAGGCGUGCUGGUCACCAUGACAACAGAGACAGGCCCCGACUCUGAGGUGAAGAAAGCUCAGGAGGAGGCCCCGCAGCAGCCCGAGGCUGCUGCCGCUGUGACCACCCCUGUGACCCCUGCAGGCCACGGCCACCCAGAGGCCAACUCCAAUGAGAAGCAUCCAUCCCAGCAGGACACGCGGCCUGCUGAACAGAGCCUAGACAUGGAGGAGAAGGACUACAGUGAGGCCGAUGGCCUUUCGGAGAGGACCACGCCCAGCAAGGCCCAGAAAUCGCCCCAGAAGAUUGCCAAGAAAUACAAGAGUGCCAUCUGCCGGGUCACUCUGCUUGAUGCCUCGGAGUAUGAGUGUGAGGUGGAGAAACAUGGCCGGGGCCAGGUGCUGUUUGACCUGGUCUGUGAACACCUCAACCUCCUAGAGAAGGACUACUUCGGCCUGACCUUCUGUGAUGCUGACAGCCAGAAGAACUGGCUGGACCCCUCCAAGGAGAUCAAGAAGCAGAUCCGGAGUAGCCCCUGGAAUUUUGCCUUCACAGUCAAGUUCUACCCGCCUGAUCCUGCCCAGCUGACAGAAGACAUCACAAGAUACUACCUGUGCCUGCAGCUGCGGGCAGACAUCAUCACGGGCCGGCUGCCAUGCUCCUUUGUCACGCAUGCCCUACUGGGCUCCUACGCUGUGCAGGCUGAGCUGGGUGACUAUGAUGCUGAGGAGCAUGUGGGCAACUAUGUCAGCGAGCUCCGCUUCGCCCCUAACCAGACCCGGGAGCUGGAGGAGAGGAUCAUGGAGCUGCAUAAGACAUAUAGGGGGAUGACCCCGGGAGAAGCAGAAAUCCACUUCUUAGAGAAUGCCAAGAAGCUUUCCAUGUACGGAGUAGACCUGCACCAUGCCAAGGACUCUGAGGGCAUCGACAUCAUGUUAGGCGUUUGUGCCAAUGGCCUGCUCAUCUACCGGGACCGGCUGAGAAUCAACCGCUUUGCCUGGCCCAAGAUCCUCAAGAUCUCCUACAAGAGGAGUAACUUCUAUAUCAAGAUCCGGCCUGGGGAGUAUGAGCAAUUUGAGAGCACAAUUGGCUUUAAGCUCCCAAACCACCGGUCAGCCAAGAGACUGUGGAAGGUCUGCAUCGAGCAUCAUACAUUCUUCCGGCUGGUGUCCCCUGAGCCCCCACCCAAGGGCUUCCUGGUGAUGGGCUCCAAGUUCCGGUACAGUGGGAGGACCCAGGCACAGACUCGCCAGGCCAGCGCCCUCAUUGACCGGCCUGCACCCUUCUUUGAGCGUUCUUCCAGCAAACGGUACACCAUGUCCCGCAGCCUUGAUGGAGCAGAGUUCUCCCGCCCAGCCUCGGUCAGCGAGAACCAUGAUGCAGGGCCUGACGGUGACAAGCGGGAUGAGGAUGGCGAGUCUGGGGGGCAACGGUCAGAGGCUGAGGAGGGAGAGGUCAGGACUCCAACCAAGAUCAAGGAGCUAAAGCCGGAGCAGGAAACCACGCCGAGACACAAGCAGGAGUUCUUAGACAAGCCAGAAGAUGUCUUGCUGAAGCACCAGGCCAGCAUCAAUGAGCUCAAAAGGACCCUGAAGGAGCCCAACAGCAAACUCAUCCACCGGGAUCGAGACUGGGAACGGGAGCGCAGGCUGCCCUCCUCCCCCGCCUCCCCCUCCCCCAAGGGCACCCCUGAGAAAGCCAAUGAGAGAGCAGGGCUGAGGGAGGGCUCCGAGGAGAAAGUCAAACCACCACGUCCCCGGGCCCCAGAGAGUGACACAGGCGAUGAGGACCAGGACCAGGAGAGGGACACGGUGUUCCUGAAGGACAACCACCUGGCCAUUGAGCGCAAGUGCUCCAGCAUCACGGUCAGCUCUACGUCUAGCCUGGAGGCUGAGGUGGACUUCACGGUCAUUGGUGACUACCAUGGCAGCGCCUUCGAAGACUUCUCCCGCAGCCUGCCUGAGCUCGACCGGGACAAAAGCGACUCGGACACUGAGGGCCUGCUGUUCUCCCGGGAUCUCAACAAGGGGGCCCCCAGCCAGGAUGAUGAGUCUGGGGGCAUUGAGGACAGCCCGGAUCGAGGGGCCUGCUCCACCCCGGAUAUGCCCCAGUUUGAGCCCGUGAAAACAGAAACCAUGACUGUCAGCAGUCUGGCCAUUAGAAAGAAGAUUGAGCCGGAGGCCGUACUGCAGACCAGAGUCUCCGCUAUGGAUAACACCCAGGUUGAUGGGAGUGCCUCAGUGGGGAGGGAGUUCAUAGCAACCACUCCCUCCAUCACCACGGAGACCAUAUCGACCACCAUGGAGAACAGUCUCAAGUCCGGGAAGGGGGCAGCUGCCAUGAUCCCAGGCCCACAGACGGUGGCCACGGAAAUCCGUUCUCUUUCUCCGAUCAUCGGGAAAGAUGUCCUCACCAGCACCUACGGCGCCACUGCGGAAACCCUCUCAACCUCCACCACCACCCAUGUCACCAAAACUGUGAAAGGAGGGUUUUCUGAGACAAGGAUCGAGAAGCGAAUCAUCAUUACUGGGGAUGAAGAUGUCGAUCAAGACCAGGCCCUGGCUUUGGCCAUCAAGGAGGCCAAACUGCAGCAUCCUGAUAUGCUGGUAACCAAAGCUGUCGUAUACAGAGAAACAGACCCAUCCCCAGAGGAGAGGGACAAGAAGCCACAGGAAUCCUGACCUCUGUGAAGAGAUCCUGGCAUUUCUGGUCCAACCCAAGCCAGAGAACCAUUAAGAAGGGGCCUUCAUUCUGGAUUCUCCGACGCAACACUGACGUCCCAGCUGCGACGUACUGUCACUGAUGAGAGACUGGGAAGGGAAAAGCAUAUAUAUAUAGAUAUAUAGAGAUAUAGAUAUAUAUACAGGAAACACCGCAUCCUUGCACUGCUGCUGGGGCUGGCAGAGCAGUUGGCUGACAGCAACAACCGACAUCUGAACACCUACAUUUCCUUUGCAGACAAAUUGAAGAACUGGUGGGAUUUUUUUCAAGAAAAAAAAUUAUAUAAUAACUAUAAUCCCUUGCUCACCCCUUUCCCCCGCCAAAUAAGAAACGCAAGCCAGACCACGAUGAUUGUAGAAGUCCCUCCCGCCCUGGUUCUGCACGUUACAGUUAGCAGACGAGCAAUUCCAUUUGUUCUUCUCCAGCAUCUCUAAGGCCCACUUGAAUGCAAAGGAAAACACUUGCACAGCAAAGCAAGAGAAGUCACAGCAGCAAGACACGCACAGUCAACCAUUUUCCGAGAAAAAAAGAAAAUUCCCCACUUGGAAAGAAAGAGGAGGAACACUGGAUUCUUACUUUCUGGAUCUUGACACUGGGCUGCAAAACCUACCUUCCUCUCUCCCGCCUCCCCUCACCCUCAACUCUCAAUGUCUUGCUGUCAUUUUCUGUCUCGGCUCCCUCCUCCCCCUUCCCCCUUCCCCCACCCCACACCCUUCACCCUCUGUGUCCUGGUCCUUCUGAGGGCCACUGCAGAUGACUCUCCUUUGAAAUGAGAAAAAGAAAAGAAAGCAAGAACAGAAAACGAAGCCACAGGAAGGGAAGUAGACAUUGUAUGCUUAUGGUUUCUCAUUAUGAAGGUGCAGCUUGUAGGAGGUUUGUACGGAUGUGCUUUGAAGUUAUGUAUAUUACAUAUAACAGGAAAAAAUAUUAAAAUAAACAGUGCUGGUAAGUAUGAAGCUGACAUUCUAAAAUUAUAAUUAUCUGACUGUGAUUGAUGUAUCCUGAGGUUCCUAGAUCUCACUGAACUGGCCCAGCUAAGGAGACCUGGACUCUGGGUGUGGGUUGGCUCACAGUAGGGGCUGACGGGUUCAGUGUAGUAAUACUGUGUGUGGUGUUUGUAAUUGGUUGAUUGGUGGGGAGGGGUGGGGGGCCCUAAUGGAGAGGUGUGGGUUUGGCAAGAAAGAAGCAACACAGAUGUCGUCCCCAAAAUGCCAGUUCAAGACACCUUCUCCCUGCCCCCCUGGUAGUAACAGUCAGGGCCUGGUCUGUGCUCAGGUACUGGGUCCCAGUCUGGGACUCUGCUGCUGAAGUUGCCACAGUAGAGGUCCCUGGCUUAGUCCUUAUCUCCCUACGGGGCUUGCCUUGGUUUUCAGUCUUCUCUCUCUUUCUCUCUUUUUUUUUUUUUUGCCACAUUCUGCCCUUCCCUGACCCCAUUGUAAUAACCAACUCCAUAUCCAAAGGGAGGUGGUGCUCUCAGCCAUUGUAGAAGAUGGUGGCUUUAACCUGACUGUCUAAAAAUUCCCAGCUAAGCCUUUUCCUCUACUCUCUUCCUUGUUCUGAAUCAUUUCUUCUUCUCAGGCCAAAGUAGCCAUGGUAAGGAGGCUUCAUGGGGCAGACCCUGAAAGAUCAAAACUGCAUUUGCAAAGCCCUCCCCUGUCCCAGGACAAAGCUGAGACUGACGGGUGAUGUUGCUCAUAGGCUCCAGCUCUGCAUAAGACCUUGGCUUGGAGACCUCCCUCUCAGUCAACAGCUGAACUCUGAGCUUGUGCCCAGAAAUUACCCCAAGACCACAGGAACCCUUCAAGAAGCUCCCAUCACAAGCUUGGCAUUGCUCUCUGCCACACGUGGGCUUCCUCAGGCUUGUCUGCCACAAGCUACUUCUCUGAGCUCAGAAAGUGCCCCUUGAUGAGGGAAAAUGUCCCACUGCACUGCGAAUUUCUCAGUUCCAUUUUACCUCCCAGUCCUCCUUCUAAACCAGUUAAUAAAUUCAUUCCACAAGUAUUUACUGAUUACCUGCUUGUGCCAGGGACUAUUCUCAGGCUGAAGAAGGUGGGAGGGGAGGGCGGAACCUGAGGAGCCACCUGAGCCAGCUUUAUAUUUCAACCAUGGCUGGCCCAUCUGAGAGCAUCUCCCCACUCUCGCCAACCUAUCGGGGCAUAGCCCAGGGAUGCCCCCAGGCGGCCCAGGUUAGAUGCGUCCCUUUGGCUUGUCAGUGAUGACAUACACCUUAGCUGCUUAGCUGGUGCUGGCCUGAGGCAGGGCAGGAAAUCAGAAUAGCAUUUGCUUCUCUGGGCAAAUGGGAAGUUCAGCGGGGCAGCAGAAUCAGUGGCAUUCCCCCUGGUGCAGGCCGGUGGGUCCACUCCAACUCCCCCUGAGUGUAGCAGCACACUUUCCAUACACCAGGUUCUUUCUACAAUCCUGGUGGAAAAGCCACAGAACCUUCUUCCUGCCCUUCUUGAGAGUUCCCCCUCUUUCUGGGUCAAGAGCUGGAGUGGUGGCUCCAUCCUCUCUGGGCCACUUCGGUCUAGGAACUCAUCUUUGCAGGAACCAGGAGUCCUGAGCACACUGAACACACCUCAGAGGGAGGAUCCUUGUUGUGGAUUUUGCACCUGGCUUUGGGGCAGGGGUGAAGUGACCAGGCUUAGCUUGUGGAGUUUAUGGGCCACCAGGGUUUGGGGAAAUCACCAUCCCGCGGAUGCUGUGACCUCCCUUCUACGGAGAUGCAGGCAGUGCCACGAGGGAGGAGGGGACCUGCAAAGCUAGAAUCUAGGGCACUGUUUCCUCCCCAUCCUUCUCUUUGUAGAGAAUAGAGACGUUUGUCUUGUCUGUCUUCAACCUACUUUUCCUUUUCUCUUUUUUGUUUCUCAUCCUCUCUGUGCCACCUCUCCACCCAGGAGGCCAUGUAGCAUAGUGGAAAAAGUCCCUGAGGGCGGUUAGGAGUUCUGGGUGACCAUCCUGGCUCAGCUCCUAACUCACCAUGUGACAUCAGGCUAUCCCCAUUCCCCCUCUUGGGCCUCAGUUUCCCGACUUGCAAAAUAAGCAGAAAGAACCAGAUGCUCUCCAGGGUCUUUUUCUACUUUGCUAUCUCAUGGGUCUUCAUUUUCUCUUAUUUUGUUUUCUCUGGAUCUUUUCCAUCUGAGGGUACAGGAAGUACCAGGACCUGUUUCAGUUUUUGAAUCCUGCAAGCACAUUCCAAGACUGGCCUGAAACUGCAUGAGCAACAUCACUCGAAAUAAUUUUUUUUUUCAAAAGCACCUUAACAACCAAUUGCGAUGCUGUCCUGUUCCUUUUUACUCACACCCUUCUCUCCUUUCUCGUCCCCAUGCUCCCCCACCUCAGUGCUCCGUGCUGUAUGCGUGUGCUCUCUGUUCUUGUAUACUCAAUAUAAGUGAAAUAAAUGUGUUUGAUGCUGAACCAUA